GACUAGGAAGAGCCGAGACUGCGAAGGAGAACGCAGCAAGCCCAGGCGGCGGUGGAAAGGCUGGAGGACACACCUAAACAUGUGGAAUCCCAAUGCCGGGCAGCCAGGGCCAAAUCCAUAUCCCCCCAAUAUUGGGUGCCCUGGAGGUUCCAAUCCUGCCCACCCACCACCUAUUAAUCCACCCUUUCCCCCAGGCCCCUGUCCUCCUCCCCCAGGAGCUCCCCAUGGCAAUCCAGCUUUCCCCCCAGGUGGGCCCCCUCAUCCUGUGCCACAGCCAGGGUAUCCAGGAUGCCAACCGUUGGGUCCCUACCCUCCUCCAUACCCACCGCCUGCCCCUGGAAUCCCUCCUGUGAAUCCCUUGGCUCCUGGCAUGGUUGGACCAGCAGUGAUAGUAGACAAGAAGAUGCAGAAGAAAAUGAAGAAAGCUCAUAAAAAGAUGCACAAGCACCAAAAGCACCACAAGUACCACAAGCAUGGCAAGCAUUCCUCCUCUUCCUCCUCCUCUUCCAGCAGUGAUUCUGACUGAAUACAGGCCCUGGACCCUUCCCUCAAGUCUCACCAGUUCUGCUCUCCCAUCAAGCUUCAGAUGCCAUGUUGUACUGGGGGAAUGUAGCCCUUGUGCUCCCCACCCCCUACCUCCACCUGAGCCUCACCCUGCUGUUGAGCCCUGAGUGGCUAGGGGAAAUGGGAAGAGGAUUGCCAUGGCCUGGCCAUCUUGUUGCUGCUUGGUUAGAUCAUAUAGCUAAUGAAUUAGGCAGGGGAGCUAUUUUUUGAAGAUGAUGAACUAAAUGUUGAAGACAAGUUUGAGAUCUGUAAAAUGUGAUUUUUUACUUCCACUUAUAAUACUUGUGAUUGGGGAGGUUUGUGGAAAUUCAAUUAUGAUGAAAAACCUAUCUUUUUUGUAAUGUUGGCAUACUUGGGGAAUUUAGUGGCAAAUACAUUCCCCAGCAGGCCUUUUGUUGGUUGCACUAACUGCAAGGUUGCUGGGAAGUAGAGUCCAUUUGGUUGAUGAGCUUUGACUGCGGUUUUGGAACCUUACCUCUCCUCCUUAGCCCAAUAUGCUGUCUUGGGUCCUAUUCAAAUAAAGUUAUUUCUCCUGGUCUCA